GCACCACAAUGUCUGGCUAAUUUUUGCAUUUUUGGUAGAGACAGAGUUUUGCUGUGUUGCUCAGGCAGGUAUUGAACUCUCAGGCUCGAGCAAUCUGCCCUCCUCAGCCUCUCAAAGUGCUGGGAUUACAGGCAUGAGCCACUGCACCUUGCCCAACUGUUUUCCUUUGUAGAAACCUGCCAAAUUCUUUUCCACGGUGGCUGUGCCAUUUUGCAUUCUCACUAGCAAUGAGAAUUCUAGUACUUGGUAUUGUCAGUUAUUUUUUAUUUUACAUGUGUAGUGAUAUCACCUUUGAUUUUAAUUUUGCAUUUCCCUGAUGUCUAAUAAUAUUGAACUGUUUUCCUGUGUUUAUUUGCCAUCUGCAUAUUUUCUUUGGUGAAGUUUCCAUAUCGUUUUUCUUUUAGCCUUCUGUUUGUUUUUUUGUUGAGACAGGGUCUUGCUCUGUUACCCAGGCUGAAUGCAGUGGUGUGACCUUGGCUCACUGCUGCCUUGACCUCCCAGGCUCAAGUGAUCCUCCCAUCUCAACCUCCUGAGUAGUUGAGACCACAGGCACAUGCCACCAUGCCCACCUAAUUUUGUUUAUAUUUUUGUAGAGACAAGAUCUCAGUAUGUUGUCCAGGCUGGUCUUUAUUUCCUGGGCUCAAGUGAUCCUCCUGCCUUGGUCUCCCAAAGUGCCAGGCUUAUAGGUGUGAGCCACUAUGCCUGGACUGAAGUAUCCUUUCAAAUCUCUUUCUUAUUUUGUGGAUUAAAUACUUAAAUGUAAGACCUGAAACUGUGAAACUACUAGGCAAAAACAUUGUGGAAAUGCUUCAGGACAUUGUUCUGGGCAAAGAUUUUUUUGAGGUAAAAACUUAAAAGCACAGGCAAUAAAAGCAAAAAUAGAUGGUAUUAUAUUAAGCUAAAAAGCUUCUGUACAGCAAAGGAAAUAACCAACAGAGUAAAGAGACAACUUAUUGAAUCAGAGAAAACAUUUGCAAAAUAUCCAUCUGACGAGGGAUUAAUAACAAGAAUAUAUAAGGAGCUGAAACAAUGGCAAAAAGCCAAAUAAUCUGAUUUUUAAAAUGGGCAAAUGAUCUGAAUAGACAUUUCACAAAAGAAGAUGUACAGGUGGCCAACAGGUACAUGAAAAAAUAUUCGACAUCGUGAAUCAGGGAAAUGCAAAUCAAAACCACAAUGAGAUAUCGUCUCACCCCAGUUAAAAUGGCUAUCAAAAAGACAAAAAAAAAAAUAAAAUAAAAUAAAAAAGAUUCUUGUGAGGAUAAAGAGAAAGGGGAAUGGUAGGACAGUUUUAUUGGGAAUAUAAAUUAGUGUAGCCUCUGUAAAAAACAGUAUGGAGGUUCCUCAAAAAAAUCAAAAUAGAUCUGCCAUAUGAUCCAGCAAUUUCACCACAAAGUAUAAACUAAAAGAAAGGAAAUCAAUGUAUUGAAGAGAGAUCUGCAUUCCAGCGUUUAUUACAGUACUAUUUACAGUUUCCAAGAUACGGAAAAACCUGAAUCCAUCAGCAGACGAAUGGAUAAAGAAAAUGUAUAUAUACACGGAAUAUUAUUCAGCCAUAAAAAAGAAUGAUAUCCUGUCAUUUCCAGCAACAUGGAUGUAACUGGAGAACAUUAUGUUCAGUGAAAUAAGCCAAGCACGGACAUGUUGCAUGUUCUCACUCUUGGGAUUUAAAAAAAGUUGAUCUCGGGAAGGUAGAGAGUAGAACAAUGGUUACCAGAGGCUGGGAAGGGUAGGGGGGCAAAGGGUAGGAAGACAGAUUGGUCAAUGGGUGUAAAAAUACAGUUAGAGGCCGGGCGCAGUGGCUCAUGCCUGUAAUCCCAGCAUGGGAGGCUGAGGUGGGCGGAUCACGAGGUCAGGAGUUCGAGACCAGCCUGGCCAACAUAGUGAAACCCUGUCUCUACUAAAAAUACAAAAAUUAGCCAUGCGUGGUGGUACGUGACUAGUCCCAGCUACUUGGGAGGCUGAGGCAGGAGAAUCGCUUGAAGUCAGGAGGCGGAGGUUGCCGUGAGUCGAGAUAGCGCCGCUGCACUCCAGCCUGGGCGACAGAGCUAGAAUGCUGUCUUAAAAAAAAAAAAAAACAAUUGGAAUAAGUUCUAGUGUUUGAUAGCACUGCAUUGUGGCUAUAGUUAACAAUAAUUUAUUAUUUCAAAAUAGAAGAGAAGGUUUGGAAUGUUCUCUACAGAAAGAAAUGAUAAAUGUGUGAAGUGAUAGAUAUCCUAAUUACCCUGAUUUGAUCAUUACACACUGUAUGUAUGUAUCGGAAUAUCAUGUGUACUCCAUAUAUAUGUAGGUUAUUAUGUAUCAAUAAAAAGUAUUUUGCUCAUUUUAAUAUUUGUUUUCUUUCUUUCUUUCUUUUUAUUUAUUUAUUUAUUUUUUUGAGACGGAGUUUUGCUCUUGUUGCCCAGGCUGGAGUGCAAUGGUACGAUCUUGGCUCACCACAACCCCCGCCUCCUGGGUUCAAGAAAUUAUCUUGCCUCAGCCUCCAGAGUAGCUGGGAUUACAGGCGUGUCCCACCAUGCCCAACUGAUUUUGUAUUUUUAGUAGAGACGGGGUUUCUCCACGUUGGUCAGGCUGGUCUCGAACUCCCGACCUCAGGUGAUCCACCCGCCUCAGCCUCCCAAAGUGUUGGGAAUAUAGGCCUGAGCUACUGCGCCUGGACGAUAUUUGUUUUCUUACUGAAUUUUAAAAAUUCUUUGGAUAUUCAGGAUAUUUCUCUUGUCAAUUAGAUGUUUCUUUUAGACUAAUAUGCAUGUGUGUGUGUCUUGUCUUUUUAUAUUCCUAACAGUGUCUUUCAUAGAACAGACGUUUUAAAUUUCUUUCUUUUAUGCAUCAUGGAUCAUGCUUUUGAUGUCAUUUUUCUUUUUUUUUUUUUAACUAAUAUUUUUUAGAGACAGGUUCUCACUUUGUGUCCAGGGUAGGGUGCAGUGGCACAAACAUGGCUGACUACAGCCUCAACCUCCUGGGCUCAAGGAAUCCUUCCAUUUUAGCCUCCCAAGUUGCUGGGACUACAAAUGUAUGCCACCAUACCCCAGUUUGUUUUAAAAAUUUUUUGUAGAAAUGGGGUCUUGCUAUGUUGCCCAGGUUGCUCCUGAACUUUUGUCCUCAGGUGAUGCUCCCACCUUGGCCUCCCAAAGUGCUAGGAUUAUAGGCAUGAGCCACCACGUCCAGCCUGGUGUCAUUUUUCUAGGAAAACUUUUAGGAAACCAAGGUCACAAAGAUUUUUUCUGCAAACUUUUCUUAUACAUAUUUUGUAGUUUUAGUUUUUACACUUGGCUCUGUGAUCCAUUUUGAGGUAAUUUUUAUUUGUUGAAUUACUUCUACAACUUUGUGGAAAAUCAAUUGAUCAUAUAUAUGUGUGUCUAUUUGUAGACUGUCCUUUCUUCCUAUUUUCCAGUAUGUUAAUCCUUUUGUCAGCAUCUCACUGUUGAUUAUUGUAGUUUUAUAUGAAGUGUCGAUGUUAUAUAGUGUGAAUCCUCCAACUUUGUUUUUCUUUUUCAAAAUUGUCUUGGCAAUUCUAGUUCCUUUGCCGUUCCAUAUAAAUUUUAGAAUCAGUUUGUUAUUUUUUAUAAAAAGAUUGCUGGGGAUUUGAAUGGAAUUGCAUUGAAUCUAUAGAUGAAUUUGGGGAGAACUAAAACCUUAACCAGGUAAACUCUUCUAAUCCAUGAACACAUCCAUAUCUCUCCAUUUGCUUAGGUUGUUUUUAAUUUCUUUAAUCUGUAAUUUAUAGUUUUCAGCAUAGUGUUUGCCUUUUAGGUGCUAUUAUAAAAUACACUGUUUUGUCCGUUGCUUGUGCAGUUGGCAACCUUAUUUGAAGGUUUAAAGACACCUCAUUUAAUAUAUAUCAUUGAAUCAUUAACAUUGAACUUACACAGCCAACAGUGCUGUAACUCAUGCCUGAAUAAGCUUAUCUAAAAUACAUAUUUUCUCCACAAGACAGAUCACAGCUUUCUUGUGCUUAGGUACACUAGGUAGCACUUGAGCACUGUGCCAGGGAUCCAUUUUAAACAUCAAAACUACUGGAAAAAAAAAAAAGCAUAAAAACAUGGCACUAAGUAGAGCACUAAAAGGAGACUUGUUUAUUGUAUGAGACCUGAACCAAAAAGGCACAAUAUCACUUUGACCUCAGCUGGGAAUGUGCAUGUUGGGUGACUCAGGUUUUUCACUGCUCUGCACAUGUUCAUGAAUGACCACGAGAGUGCAGUAAAUAUUGAUUUUGGGAUUACAAAUAAAUUUUAGUGAGUAGGCAAAUAAGGAAUCUGUGAAUGAAGAUCAAUUAUAUAAAAGUAAAAUUGACUUUUGUGCUAUAUAUUGGCCUUAUAUCUUGCUAACUCAGGUGAUAGAGCUUUUUUGUAGAUUCUUUAGCAUUUUCUUCAUCAAUAUUCAUGUCAUUGGCAAAUAGGGGUACUUUUAUUAUUCCUUUUUUCUCUCUUCCAUCUUUUUCUCUUUUUAAAAUUGUAGUGAAAAGCACAUCAAAUAAAUUUACCUACUGGUCUGAUUGCAGUGAUGUUUACAACUAAUUGAUCACAACCAAUUAUAGAUUUCUUUAUUCCUUCUCCAUUUCCAGUGCUUUACUUGAGUAGCCUAAAAAAAAAAAAUUACACUCUUAACAAAUUUUGAAUACAAUUUAUGGCAUUGUUACUUAUGUGCAUAUUGUUGUGCAACAGUUAUCUAUAACUUUUUCAUCUUGCAUUACUGAAACUACCCAUUUCUCCCUCCCCACAACACUUGACAAACACCAUUCUACUUUCCAUUUCUGUGUGCUUGAUUAUAUUAGGUACCUCAUGUAAGUGGAAUCAUGCAGUAUUUGUCCUUUUGUGAUUGGCUUAUUUUACUUAGCAUAAUGUCCUCAAGGUUAAUUUAUGUUGUGGCAUAUGAUAGGAUUUACUUCUUUUAUAAUACUGAACAUUCCAUGGUAUGUAUAUGUUAUGUUUUGUGUAUCCUUCUAUCAGUGGACAUUUCGAUUGUUUCUGUAUCGUUAAUGUGAGCAAUGCUGCAACAAACGUGGAUUGUGAGAUAUCUCUUCAAGAUCCUGUUUUCAGUUCAUUUGGAUAUACACCUAGAAGUGGGAUAAUGUGGUAGUUCUAGUUUUAAUUUUUUGAGGACGCUCUAUACUGUUUUCCAUAGUAGCUUCACCAUUUUAUAAUAAUAUUAACAGUGCACAGGGGUUUCAAUUUUCCCACAUCCUCUCCAAUACUUGUUAUUUUCUGGUUUUUUGAUAUUGGCACUUCUAACAGGUAUGAGGAUGAGAUCUCAUUGUGGUUUUGAUUUGUAUUUCUUUUAUGAUUAGUGAUGUUGAGCAUCUUUUCAUAUGCUUAUUGACCAUUGUAUAUCUUUUUAUUAUUAUUAUUAUUAUUUUUUAAGAUAGGGUCUUGCUUUGUCGCCCAGACUGGAGUGCAGUCGCACACUUACGGCUUGCUGCAGCCUUGACUUCAAGCAGUCCUCUCACCUCAGCCUCAUGAGUAGCUGGGACUACAGGCGUGCGCCACCAUGCCCGGCUAAUUUUUUUUUUUUUUUUUUGUAGAGAUGGGGUUUCGCCAUGUUGUUCAGGCUGGUCUUGAACUCUUGGGCUCAAGUGAUCCACCUGCCUCCGCCUCCCAAAGUGCUGGGAUUACAAGUGUGAGCCACUGUUAUCAGCUCAUUGUAUAUCUUUGGAGAAAUGUCUAUUCAAGCUCUUUGCCCAUUUUCAAAUUGGAUUAUUUUUUGUUGUUAAUUAUCAAGUUGAGAAGUUCUUUACAUAUUCUGGGUAAUAACACCUUAUCUGAUAUGUGGUUUGCAAAUAUUUUCUCCCAUUCCAUAAAUUGUCUUUUUACUCUGUUGAUUGUGUCCUUUGGUGCACAGAAGUUUUUCAGUUUGAUGUAGUCCCAUUUGUCUAUUUUUGCUUUUGUUACCUGUACUUUUGGUGUCAUAUCCAAGAAAUCAUAGCCCAUUUCAAUGUCAUGAAGCUUUUUCCCUAUGUUUACUUCUAGGAAUUUUAUAGUUUCAGGUGCUACCUUUAGACCUGUAAUCCAUUUUGAGUUAAUUUUUGUAUAUGGUGUGAGAUAACGUCCAUCUUUAAUCUUUUACAUGGGCAUGUCCAGUUUUCUCAACACCAUUUGCUGAAGAGAGUAUCGUUUUUCCAUUGUGGAGUCUUGGCACCAUUGUCAAAGAUUGACCAGAUACUUCCUGGGAUCAAGUGAUCCUCCCACCUCAGCCUCCCAAGUAGCUGGGACCACCAGAAGGUGACAUCACACCUGGCUGAUUUUUGUAUGUUUUGUAGAGAUGGGGUUUUGUCAUGUUGCCCAAGCUGGUCUUGAACUCCUGAGCUCAAGCGUUCUGCCCAUCUCGGCCUCCCAAGUGUUGUGAUUACAGACAUGAACCACCACGUCUAGCUCCCACAUUUUUGUUAUCUUAUAUUUUACAUCCAGCUUGUUAGGUCUUCUGAUACUUUUCUUUAUCCUUAAUGUUUUGUAUUUUGCCAUGUUACUGUGUAUAAGUGUAGAUUAAAAAAAUACUGAUUAGCAGUAGAGAGUUUUUUCAACCUAGAAAAUAAUAUCUUGGAAAAAUUUCAACCAUUAUUUAUUUAUUUAUUUUGAGAUGAAGUCUCACUGUAUCACCCAGGCUGGAGUGCAGUGGCGAGAUCUCGGCUCACCACAACCUCCGCCUCCCAGAUUCAAGCCAUUCUCCUGCCUAAGCCUCCCGAGUAGCUGGGAUUACAGGGCCAUUUCUGAGCAGUGGAGGUUUCAAGUAAUCCACUAACAACCAGUUCCAAAUUCUGUCAUCAAAUCCUGUGCUGCUGUUCCUCGUGGUAAUAGAUGCAUAUUAUUUCUUUUAUUUAAAAGAAAUGAAUGUGACUAGUAUUGCAUUAAGAGCUGAAACUUGGCUUUUAGCUGCAUGGCAUGUUAAAGUACCUCCGAUGUGGCUGGAAGCUUGUAUUAACUGGAUUCAAGAAGAAAAUAAUAAUGUUAACUUGAGUCAGGCCCAAAUGAAUAAACAAGUGUUUGAGCAGUGGCUCCUUACUGAUCUGAGGGAUUUGGAGCAUCCUCUUUUACCCGAUGGCAUUUUAGAAAUUCCAAAAGGAGAAUUAAAUGGAUUUUAUGCUCUGCAGAUUAAUUCCUUGGUUGAUGUAAGUCAGCCUGCAUACUCCCAGAUACAGAAGUUGAGAGGAAAGAAUACAACAAAUGAUCUAGUUACAGCUGAAGCACAAGUAACCCCAAAACCUUGGGAAGCAAAGCCUUCACGAAUGUUGAUGCUGCAGCUAACUGAUGGAAUCGUACAAAUACAGGGAAUGGAAUAUCAGCCUAUUCCAAUUCUUCAUAGUGAUCUUCCUCCAGGUACAAAAAUUUUGAUUUAUGGAAAUAUAUCUUUCCGUCUUGGUGUUCUCUUAUUGAAACCAGAAAACGUGAAAGUGUUAGGAGGUGAAGUAGAUGCUCUUUUAGAAGAAUAUGCCCAAGAAAAAGUACUUGCAAGAUUAAUAGGGGAACCUGAUCUUGUAGUUUCAGUCAUACCAAACAAUUCUAACGAAAACAUUCCCAGAGUUACAGAUGUUCUAGAUCCUGCAUUAGGUCCUUCUGAUGAAGAACUCUUGGCAAGUCUUGAUGAAAAUGAUGAGCUUACAGCAAAUAAUGACACUUCCUCAGAACGAUGUUUCACCACAGGUAGUUCCUCAAAUACCAUUCCCACAAGACAGUCAAGUUUUGAGCCAGAAUUUGUUAUUUCUCCAAGACCAAAAGAGGAACCAUCAAACCUAUCUAUACAUGUAAUGGAUGGAGAAUUAGAUGACUUUUCACUGGAGGAGGCCUUGCUUUUAGAAGAAACUGUCCAGAAAGAACAGAUGGAAACUAAGGAAUUGCAACCAUUGACUUUUAACAGAAAUGCCGAUCGAAGUAUAGAGAGAUUUUCACAUAAUCCUAAUACUACGAAUAACUUUUCUUUGACUUGCAAAAAUGGAAACAAUAAUUGGAGUGAAAAAAAUGUAUCUGAACAAAUGACUAAUGAAGACAAAUCAUUUGGUUGUCCAUCUGUUAGAGACCAAAACAGGAGUAUUUUUUCAGUUCAUUGUAAUGUACCCUUAGCCCAUGAUUUUACAAAUAAAGAAAAGAACUUAGAGACAGAUAAUAAAAUAAAACAAACCAGCAGUUCAGAUAGCCAUUCCUUAAAUAAUAAAAUAUUAAAUAGAGAGGUGGUCAACUAUGUACAGAAAAGGAAUUCACAAAUUUCUAAUGAAAAUGAUUGUAAUUUACAGAGUUGUUCUUUAAGAUCAUCAGAGAAUAGCAUUAAUCUUUCUAUUGCCAUGGAUUUGUAUUCUCCACCCUUUGUCUAUUUGUCUGUUCUAAUGGCCAGCAAACCAAAGGAAGUUACAACAGUGAAAGUGAAAGCAUUUAUUGUAACCUUAACUGGAAAUCUCUCAAGUUCUGGUGGUAUUUGGAGUAUAACUGCAAAGGUGUCUGAUGGUACUGCAUAUCUAGAUGUAGACUUUGUGGAUGAAAUACUUACUAGCUUGAUAGGGUUCUCAGUACCAGAAAUGAAACAGUCAAAAAAGGAUCCUCUUCAAUACCAAAAGUUCCUGGAAGGGUUGCAGAAAUGUCAAAGAGAUCUAAUAGAUUUGUGCUGUCUAAUGACUAUUUCAUUUAAUCCUUCCUUGUCUAAAGCAAUGGUACUGGCAUUACAAGAUGUUAAUAUGGAACACCUUGAGAAUCUAAAGAAGCGGUUAAAUAAAUAAUUAAACUAAAAUAGUAUUAGGAACAAUUAAAAACAACAAGGAAAUAUUUAGAAUUUGUUCACAAUUUUACUUAUGAUACUUUGUGUAAAAAGGAAAAAUGAAAUUUCAUAGCUUAUUUCAGUUUAAUUUUAAAGUGUUUAAUCAUGUUUGUUAUAUGUGGAGCUUUUGAAAAUAAGUUAAUCUUUUUUUUUUUUUUUUUAAUGUCAGGGUAUUGCUCUGUUGCCCAGGCUAGAGUGCAGUGGCAUGAUCAUAGGUUAUUGCAUCAACCUCUUGAGCUCAAGCGAUCCUCCUGCCUUAGCCUCUUGAGUUGCUGGGACUAUAGGCAUGUACCACCAUGCCCAGCUAAUUUAUAAUUACUAUUAUUGUUUUGUAGGGACAGAGUUUUGCUAUGUUGCCCAGAUUGGUCUCAAACUCCUGGCCUCUCACUCCUGCCGUCAUGGCCUCCAAAGUUUACUUUUUUUAAAAGUAACUGUUAGAUGGAGGAAUAUGGUGACCCACUAUUGUUGAGAAAUUUGUUUUCCACUUGUCACGUCACAUAAGAUGAUUGCUAAAAUAUUGUACUGGUGUUCGGUGGUGAGUCAUAUUUUUGAAAGUUAAUAAUUAUAAAUAGGUAAUUUCCUUCUAAUAUGUUGGUACUGUCUAUGGCCAUACCACCCUGAACAUGCCUGAGCUUGUCAUAAUAUGUUGAGUACCCAAAAGAUUUGUUUAUAUUGUUAAUCUUAGGGAAAAAAAAUUAAAAUCCAGUAGAUCAGAACAUCAGGCUUUCAGAUACAAAUUGAUUUACUGGUUUUUAUUUUGCUGAUUAUAAUAUUUGGUAUAUUUAAGGUAAUCUAGUUAACUAGAUGCUAUUUCAUAGAUUAUAUUGAAUGAUUUAAAACUUUAUUUUCAAGGAUAGUUUAUUUUAAAUGGCAUAUUGAAAACAUCAUUAUUAAGAUCCAGUAGGUAGGACAUUUAUUGGAUUAAAAUGAAGCAUUUAUCUAUGUCUUUAGGUGUCAUUGUUCCCUUUCUGAAUUAGCUGUACAUAUAAGCCUUCCUUUGGUUUUAAGUACUGAUUUUUUUUUAAAAAAAAGAGGGACUGUUUACCAUUCUUCCACUGUGCUGUUAUAAAGUUGUAUUUGAAAGGUAAUGUUGUUUUUAUUAAUCUUUUGUCUUAAAAUAAUUUAAAGUGCUUUGAAUUUUAAAACAUUAAACAAAUCCUUAAAUAACAAAA